GCGCCGGAAGUGGGGUGCGGAGGUGUGCAGCGCGCUGUCAGACUGGCUCGCAGGCGGCGCGGCCGGCGGACCCGUUCGAGACAGCGCGGGCGGCUCGGGUCCCCUGGGGCUCCGCAGCAGGAGGACGCCAUGGACGACAAGGAGUUAAUUGAAUACUUUAAGUCUCAGAUGAAAGAAGAUCCUGACAUGGCCUCAGCAGUGGCUGCCAUCCGGACGUUGCUGGAGUUCUUGAAGAGAGAUAAAGGGGAGACAAUCCAGGGUCUGAGGGCGAAUCUCACCAGUGCCAUAGAAACCCUGUGUGGUGUGGACUCCUCUGUGGCAGUGUCCUCUGGCGGGGAGCUCUUCCUCCGCUUCAUCAGUCUUGCCUCCCUGGAAUACUCCGAUUACUCCAAAUGUAAAAAGAUCAUGAUUGAGCGGGGAGAACUUUUUCUCAGGAGAAUAUCACUGUCAAGAAACAAAAUUGCAGAUCUGUGCCAUACUUUCAUCAAAGAUGGAGCGACAAUAUUGACUCACGCCUACUCCAGAGUGGUCCUGAGAGUCCUGGAAGCAGCCGUGGCGGCCAAGAAGCGAUUUAGUGUAUACGUCACAGAGUCACAGCCUGAUUUGUCAGGUAAGAAAAUGGCCAAAGCCCUCUGCCACCUCAACGUCCCUGUCACUGUGGUGCUAGAUGCUGCUGUCGGCUACAUCAUGGAGAAAGCAGAUCUUGUCAUAGUUGGUGCUGAAGGAGUUGUUGAAAACGGAGGAAUUAUUAACAAGAUUGGAACCAACCAGAUGGCUGUGUGUGCCAAAGCACAGAACAAACCUUUCUAUGUGGUUGCAGAAAGUUUCAAGUUUGUCCGGCUCUUUCCACUAAACCAGCAAGACGUCCCAGAUAAGUUUAAGUAUAAGGCAGACACUCUCAAGGUCGCGCAGACUGGACAAGACCUCAAAGAGGAGCAUCCGUGGGUCGACUACACUGCCCCUUCCUUAAUCACUCUGCUGUUUACAGACCUGGGCGUGCUGACACCCUCAGCAGUCAGCGAUGAGCUCAUCAAGCUCUAUCUGUAACCUGUGAGCCCUUUCCUGCCAAGGUGCAGCUUACGUAGUUGAGGCAGGGUGAGUAGCUGCUUGACACCCCAGUGAGUCAGGCCAAAACUGAGAUGUGUUUAAUGAAGAUUUAUGGAGUAAGGACUUAAAAUCAUACAUCUUGGAGAACCUUUCUUACUCAUUUCAGUCCCAUCUAAAAAUGUGUCAGCUAUUCUAAAUCCCAACUUAAAUUGUUCUUACGGUUUCUAGAAACUUUCCUUUUCAGUUUCCAGAAAUACAAGUUAGAUAAUUGGCUACUUAACUGAUGAAAGAUGAGCCCAAGUCCACCUGUCUUCAUCCUCCCCUGCACUCCAGACUGAUCUGCCUAAAGCACGCGAGAUGCAGGCGAAAAGCAGCCACACCCCUCUGCCACAAAUGACCAACAGCUGGUCAGGACGUUACACGCGGUGCCUUGUAAGAGGCAAGAAACACUUGCUGAAUCUGCAUCUGGCUUCCAGUGGUAAGCACAUUCCUCAGCAGGAUCAAGCCAAACAGUAAAAACUACCAAGAGAACACGAGGAAGGCAGAAACGAUGUUUAGCAACAGUAUUCUGCAUGGUUCACUGCUUAAGAAAAUGCCUUCUGGAAUAUUUGUAAACUGAAAUUCUGUAUGUGUAAGAGAUGUUUAAAUAUGUUUGGGUCCUAAACAGCUUUUUAAAAUUAUACUUGGGAAUAAAUUCAGCAUCUUUUCAAAUAAACUCUAUGAAAGACGCUGAUGUGGUGUUGCAUCAAUACUGCAAGCUGACCAGGCCAUCUAGGGGAAAACACUGUCCAGCUACAUUUACACACUUAAGACCCAGGCAAUCAGGACACCAUUUAUUCAACAGGAGGCAUAAAAACUAUAAUUCUCUUUCCCGGAAUAUGACUUAAUCCCUCUGUUUUUCAGCUAUUCACCAAUAAAACAAUACUGUGACUAUUAACACAGAAAAACCCCAGCACAUUAGCCACCCCUGCAGGACAUCAAAGGAUAACUGAAGCCCAGGGCCAAGCACAUUCAGGAGGUCAAAUGCCUGAAGAUACUGAGGAAUGGUUUUGAAAAUCAGAAGUCAAGAAGACUUCUGUAUCUUUAUGUUUAAAAAUAACUAUAAAAUAGCCUCAGAAAAAAGAGCUUAUAUAUAUAUAUAUAUAUAUAUAUAUAUAUAUAUAUAUAUAUAUAUAAUAUGUACAUAUGUCUAUAUGUGACCCAUCAUGAUAAAUACUGACAUCUAUUAUUUACACUCAAAUAAUUUUACAUUUUCUUCUGUUAGACUACUCCAAGACUGGAAUUGUUUUGUUUUGUUGUUUUUAAUGAGAGGGUCUCGCUGUGUUCCCAGGCUGGUCUUGAACUCCUGGG